GCACCGCCCCCGCCCGCAAGAAAGAUGGCAGUGGCCUGAUCCGGGCCCGUUGGCGGCGUCACUGACGCUUCGCUCCGGUCCUCGGAUCCCGAGCGCGGGGAGGCAGACCGACUGUGAGCUGCUUGUCCCCAUCCUGCGGCCGUCCUGGGGACACAGAGCCCUCCGUGGUGCCCGGGGAUUGGAUUGGAGCCAGGACCUCACUUCCUCCUCUGCCCCUGCCCCUGCCCCUCCCAGCACCUGGCCCACACCCUGCAGCCCGCCCCAUGGUCUGGCCCUGGGUGGCGAUGGCGUCCAGGUGGGGUCCCCUCAUUGGCCUGGCUCCGUGCUGCCUCUGGCUCCUGGGGGCAGUCCUUCUGAUGGACGCGUCUGCACGGCCUGCCAACCACUCGUCCACUCGAGAGAGAGUAGCCAACAGGGAGGAGAAUGAGAUCCUGCCCCCAGACCACCUGAACGGGGUGAAGCUGGAGAUGGACGGGCACCUCAAUCGCGGCUUCCACCAGGAGGUCUUCCUAGGCAAGGACCUGGGUGGCUUUGAUGAGGACGCGGAGCCGCGGCGGAGCCGGAGGAAGCUGAUGGUCAUCUUUUCCAAGGUGGAUGUGAACACUGACCGGAAGAUCAGUGCCAAGGAGAUGCAGCGCUGGAUCAUGGAGAAGACGGCCGAGCACUUCCAGGAGGCCAUGGAGGAGAGCAAGACACACUUCCGCGCCGUGGACCCUGACGGGGACGGUCACGUGUCUUGGGACGAGUAUAAGGUGAAGUUUUUGGCGAGUAAAGGCCAUAGCGAGAAGGAGGUUGCCGACGCCAUCAGGCUCAACGAGGAACUCAAAGUGGAUGAGGAAAGACAUGGCCCACCUGGACCUAGAGCUCUGUGACAUUUCUGUGAAGCCUCCGUCUACCUUUGGGACUCAGCAGAGGUGUGUUUAGAAUUCACUCUGCGUUUUGGGGGUCCCCAUGCAUGCUGAGGUGCUGUUCCCUGCCCACCCGUGUCCGAUCCGUCUUGGCCUCCCCGACCUCAGGGUGCCUAGGACCCCCCGACCUCUUUGGGUAUUUGGUUUCUGGCUCAGGAAGAGCAGCUGCCGGGUCCUGGAGGAGGGGCCUGGGAAGCGCUGGCAGGCGUCACUCCUGCGACCUCCCACCCCUCCCUGCAUGGCUCCUGCGAGGGUCACCGCGUGAGUCCGGGGGCUGCUGUCCUCGCGCCUCAGACCUGAUUCUGGGGACCGCGGUGAAGGCGUGGCAGGCGGGCAUCACUCCCUUCCCCCGCCUCCAUCGCUGCCUCUCUCUGGGUCUGCGUCCUCUUCUCACAGGGACAGCAGUCGUUGACUCUCCCUGAUCCAGGAGGGUCUCUCCAGAUCCUUCCCUAACAGCAGAGGCCCGGCUCGUGGGGAGGGACUGGGACUCAAGGCUUCUUCACCAGCCUGAGGUUGGUGCUGGGGCUCGGCGGCGGCUGUGAGAAUCCUGUGCUGGAGAAAGCGUCUCUCGGCCGGCCUGUCUGGGGCGUCUGUGCCUCUCCUGGAUGGGUCUCAGUUUGGCCCCGUCCAUCCAUCCCAGGAGCUGCGGUGGAGCAGACAGGGAGGGGUGCCCCAGGAACCACAGCCCCGUCACUCCUGUCUUCCUUUAAGUGAACCGGUCGUGUAGAUGGAGGUUGUUCAGAAAGGGAUAAGAUGGGACGGCAGCUGGGCCUCAUCCCGCAGUGAGCGCGACGCAGAGGCUGCCGGGCUUGUGGCAGGGGCUUCGGCCAGGGCAGAGUCGGGCCUCACGUGCAGGGGGCUGAGUGUGGGCCUCAACACUGGACUUGGCCACUGACUGCAGUGAGCCCCAAGAUGGGGCAGGAGGUGGUGUUUCUGUCCUGGAGACCCAGGGUGGCUUGGGUCCUUGGGAUGUGUGGGGACCUCGGGGUGAGGGCCCGUUGGGGCCGGGUGGGCACGGCAGGAGAGCGGGGGCCACACACCCAGAGGCAGUGCCGUGUCCCGGCUGGGAGGGUUCCUGGGAAGCUCUGCUCAGCCCCAGUCUCAGUCAUUUCUAGAAACUGUGUUUUCCUCCCUGUGACGUCACACGUGAAGGAAACGGAAAAGGGCAGUGAGUCCUUCGCCCCGCGGCGCCGUGCGCACGUCAGCCUUCAGGGUGAUUCCGCUCCUCCAGAGGGGCAGGCGCGGGUGUGGGGGGUGGGGCCCAGGCCCAUCCUGAGGGGUCCCAGGCAUGAGGGGCUCUGAGCUGUGUCCUGGGGUGGUCUGGGCCAUGGGGAGGUUCUGGAUCAUGUCUUGAGAGGUCUGGGCUGUGUGGGGGGUCCAGGCCAUGUCCUGGGGGUCUGGGCUGUGUCUGUGGGGAGUCAGGGCCAUCCAUGUAUUGGGGGUCUGGGGCAGGGGGGGGUCCAGGCUGUCUUGGGGAGUCCGGGCUGUGUGGAGGGGUCCAAGCUAUGCCUUUGGGGAUCAGGCCUGUGGGAGGCUCUGGGUUAUGUCUUGGCGGGGGUCCAGGCUGUGUCUUAGGGGCUGGGCCAUGUUCUGGGGACGUGUGAAUCCUGGAGGGUGGGGCCCCGGUCUCGCGGGUGGCUGUGUCCCUCGAGUUCAGGCAGCACCUCUCGGAACUUUCUGGAUUUGCGUGCUGGCGUCUGUCGGCCUCGAUACCCACAGGCUGCGCCCC